AGCGUGGGAUUCCGGACUGUGAGCGGCUGUUAGUGCGUCGCAGCUGCUGGCGAUCCGGCGACCCUCGGCCGGCAGGACCCGCGGGCCACGCAGCCGGGGCCUUCUCAACGCCUCAGUACCUCGGCGGGACCGCCAUGGUUCUGCUGCACGUGAAGCGGGGCGACGAGAGCCAGUUCCUGCUGCAGGCGCCUGGGAGUACCGAGCUGGAGGAGCUCACGGUGCAGGUGGCCCGGGUCUAUAAUGGGCGGCUCAAGGUGCAGCGCCUCUGCUCAGAAAUGGAAGAAUUAGCCGAACAUGGCAUAUUUCUCCCUCCUAAUAUGCAAGGACUGACCGAUGAUCAGAUUGAAGAAUUGAAAUUGAAGGAUGAAUGGGGUGAAAAAUGCGUACCCAGCGGAGGUGCAGUGUUUAAAAAGGAUGAUAUUGGACGAAGGAAUGGGCAAGCUCCAAAUGAGAAGAUGAAGCAAGUGUUAAAGAAGACUAUAGAAGAAGCCAAAGCAAUAAUAUCUAAGAAACAAGUGGAAGCCGGUGUCUGUGUUACCAUGGAGAUGGUGAAAGAUGCCUUGGACCAGCUUCGAGGCGCGGUGAUGAUUGUUUACCCCAUGGGGUUGCCACCGUAUGAUCCCAUCCGCAUGGAGUUUGAAAAUAAGGAAGACUUGUCGGGAACACAGGCAGGGCUCAACGUCAUUAAAGAGGCAGAGGCGCAGCUGUGGUGGGCAGCCAAGGAGCUGAGAAGAACGAAGAAGCUUUCAGACUACGUGGGGAAGAAUGAAAAAACCAAAAUUAUCGCCAAGAUUCAGCAAAGGGGACAGGGAGCUCCAGCCCGAGAGCCUAUUAUUAGCAGUGAGGAGCAGAAGCAGCUGAUGCUGUACUAUCACAGAAGACAAGAGGAGCUCAAGAGAUUGGAAGAAAAUGAUGAUGAUGCCUAUUUAAACUCACCAUGGGCGGAUAACACUGCUUUGAAAAGACAUUUUCAUGGAGUGAAAGACAUAAAGUGGAGACCAAGAUGAAGUUCACCAGCUGAUGACACUUCCAAAGAGAUUAGCUCACCUUUCUCCUAGGCAAUUAUAAUUUAAAAAAAAAAAAAAGGCCACUUACUGCCCUCUGUAAAAGAUGUUAACAUUUCUAGUUUUCUUUUAGUGUGAAUUUUUAAAAUAGCAGUUAUUCAAGGUUUUAGAACUUAAUAAAUACCUAGUCAGAAGAAAAUGUGUAAAUCGUUUUUGUUUCAGGACUAUUUAGUAUGUCAUGGUUUUCUUUGAUAAAAUACUAAACUUUUGGCCGGGCGCGGUGGCUCACGCCUGUAAUCCCAGCACUUUGGGAGGCCGAGGCAGGCAGAUCACGAGGUCAGGAGAUCAAGACCAUCCAGGCUAACACGGUGAAACCCCGUCUCUACUAAAAAUACAAAAAAUUAGCCGGGCAUGGUGGCAGGCGCCUGUAGUCCCAGCUACUCGGGAGGCUGAGGCAGGAGAAUGGCGUGAACCCGGGAGGUGGAGCUUACAGUGAGCCAAGAUCACUGCCACUGCACUCUAUCCUGGGCAACAGAGCGAAACUCUUGUCUCAAAAAAAAAAAAAAAAAAAAAAAAAGCUACACUUUUUUUUCUUCCUGAUUGUUUUAUAUUCUCAUGAUAACUGGUUUAUUGGAGGAAAGCUGAUGACUGGCAGUGACCACUAGUGACCACUAGAUGCCGCCAGGCACUCAGCAUGCUUUUUCUCCUGGCCCUCUAGAUCUAUUGGAAGCUGAACUCCCAGCCUUGCUGGAGAGACUUCUCUAACCCUGCUGCGGGGUCUAACUGUAGCCUUCUUUAACCCUGCUGCGGGGUCUAACUGUAGCCUUCUUUAACCCUGCUGCGGGGUCUAACUGUAGCCAGGCGUUGCCUGGCCUUGAAGGUGAAGUUUGCCUCCUGGUUGGUGCCUCUCUGGCCUUGUAUUCUGGGAGCGAAAGCUACAACCAUGAUGAAGGUUGAGUAGCAAACUCAUCUGACUUUGAAACUUAAAUUCUUCUGGAGUUUCUCAGCUUCUCAAGUCUCCUUCAUGAGAAUAGAUCCUGAAAACAAAUCCAGAUCCCGGUAGAGGGUGAUGAUUUCUCCCUAUGGAUGCGGGGUCUGAUUCUAGGCCAGCUUCGUACGCAGCUCAGUGACCAACCACGGGAUGGAUGGGAUCACUAUCAUCCUAACUGAGUAUCUAGGACACCAUUGAGUUUAAAGACUCCAACUCAUCAUCACUGUAAACCAUCCAAGUAUCCUGCAAACCCUGGCACUUUAGCAUCUGAAAGACACCUGCCAGACUGCCUGUGGCAGUCCCUCAUGCUUGACUUUUGGUGCCUAGGGUCCUGUUCUCCUGGUUAGAGGGAACUUGGUGUGCUCACACUGAGGGAAAGUGAAGGACGCGGGGCAUCUUCCUGCCCUGGCCUUCCUGCCUUGGUGCCUGCGCUCCCCACCAUCCUGCAAAGAGGAACCCUGGGAGUGAGUGGAGGUGGCAGGGGUUUGGUUCCUGCCUGCUGCCAGGCGGCCUUGCCCAGGGGGUGGGUCCCAGACCUGAGAGCAAAGCGCUGUUCUCUGAAGUGCUUUGUAGCUGACUGCAUCUUGUGCCUUACUCUUUUGGUUGAUUUUCAAAUUUUGUAAAAGCAAAUUUGCAUCUAUUUUCUCUUUUACUUGGUUAUAGUUUUAAAUGUCUCUAUGAAAGGGUUUUGACCUUGGAUGAUGUAGUAUAUGCAAUAAGAUGCUGUGAUUUUAUUUCAGGAGCAUCCUGUCUUUGUCAGUGUAUAGUUCGUGUGUGUUAAAUUCAUGCUCAGACUUGUAAGAAACAGUUAACCAAGCCAUGUGAUCAUAGUAGCUCUUUUCAGGGAACUACUACUUCAAUAUCAUUAGAAAGUCUUACUGAGCCUGCAGUAGGAAUACUCUUUUGGCCGUGAUAGUUAUCCCAUUGCUUCAUGUAAUCAGCAGAACUUACUAACCAAAAAGUCACUCACGCAUGACACUACACUCCUUAAAUACCCAUGCGAGAAGAACCAUCCUCUCUCCCUGCCCUUGUCUGCCUCAAAAGCCUCUCUGAGCUUGGUGUGUUUGGGUGCAGCAGAUCUCAGGAAGUACGUGAGUAGCUUAUUUGCAAGCCAUCUGUGACGGCGGGGGGCAGGUGGUGCCCGCUGUGGCACCGUGCUGUGUGUGUUCCCUUUGCAUCCACUUGCUGACUCACCCAAGGUCACAGGUAGCUAGUGGUGGUAGGACCACAGGGUCACGUCCAGGAACUUUCCCAGGAUUUCCCAAGAAAUCAAUUUAUCAACAAAAGUAAUCUUGCCAGUGUUAGACCACUGAUCAGCUUAAGUCUGUGGUCUUGUUGUUAUUUUCUUCUUUUUUUAAUCCAGUCCCUGUUUGAGUCAAUAUCAAAAGGAAACCAAGUGUCUGCUGUAUGCACGGUGCCCAUCUAGGUCUGUGGUUUUGUCCUUUGACAUAACUUGUCUUCUUAUGUGGUUCUUUCAUGGAGACCAGGAAUGCUAGUAAUAAAAUUUGAUACCACCUAAAA